AGUUUGAACUUGGCGGGCCAGAUGUGGGCGGCGGGGCGCUGGGGGCCUACUUUUCCCUCUUCCUACGCCGGUUUCUCUGCUGACUGCAGACCCAGGUCUCGGCCCUCCUCGGACUCCUGCUCAGUCCCUAUGACGGGCGCACGUGGGCAGGGGCUGGAGGUGGUGCGCUCGCCGUCGCCGCCGCUGCCGCUGAGCUGCAGCAAUUCCACCAGGUCGCUGUUGUCUCCCCUUGGCCACCAGAGCUUCCAGUUUGACGAGGACGACGGUGACGGGGAGGAUGAGGAAGACGUGGAUGAUGAGGAAGACGUGGAUGAAGAUGCCCAUGAUUCAGAGGCCAAAGUGGCGAGCCUGAGAGGAAUGGAGUUACAGGGGUGCGCCAGCACUCAGGUUGAAUCAGAAAAUAACCAAGAAGAACAGAAACAGGUGCGCUUACCAGAAAGCCGCCUGACACCAUGGGAGGUGUGGUUUAUUGGCAAAGAAAAAGAAGAACGUGACCGGCUGCAACUGAAAGCUCUAGAGGAAUUAAAUCAACAACUAGAAAAAAGAAAAGAAAUGGAAGAACGUGAAAAAAGAAAGAUAAUUGCUGAAGAAAAGCACAAGGAAUGGGUUCAGAAAAAGAAUGAGCAAGUAAGGAGGGGAAAAUGGAUACACACAUUGACAUCUCUUUUGCAAAAUAUUUCUUCCUAUUAUACUUCAUUACCUAGGUUUUAAAAAAUACUUCUCUUAGAGUCUUUCUUCUUUGGCUUGUUUUGUUUUUCUAUCCUGGUGGACAUUUAUCAAGUCUCUAUCUUCUGCCCUUUGCCCUCUACUUUUCUCCUUUUUCCCUCCUGUGGCUUGCACUAAUAUUUGCCUGCAGGCAGUCACCAAGUCUGUAUUUCUAGGCCUGACCUUUUGGAUCCUUAUGGCAAGUGCCUCCAAGUCUGCAAAUCUAAAACAACCCAUUUUGCCCAUUUCUCCUUCGUAAAUCCAUCCUCCCAUUUCUCUGUUUCAUUCAGCUGUCUUCUCGGUCAUCAAGGCUUAAUUAGAAUUCUUCUGUUGUUCCUAAUCAUCUCCUCCUUUUCUUUACAAUUACUACUCCCCUGUUUGUGAUCUCUUUCCAUUAUAUCUUUCAACUUGUUGUUUACUUCUUAUACUGGAUUGUAAGCUACAUAAGGGCAGGGAUUUUUGCCUCUUUUGUUCAGUUUUCCAGGAGCUAGAUGAAUACCUGCGCAUGAUAUAUGUCCAAAAAUAGUUUAAUUGAGUGAAGAUGUUCAUUGAAUGGCUGCAUUUUUUCCUUUUAAUUUUAAUAUAUUCUUCUAUGGAUCACACACAUUCGAAAUUUUAAAAAUACUUAUUCUGUGGUCAAUUUGUCUUCUGUUGUGAUUUUUACAUAUUUAGAGUGGUACUGCUUUUAUUAUUAUAAUCCAGUUUUACAAAUGUGGAAAAAUGUUUAAAUUGUAGGACAAUAUUUUAAAUUUUAAUUCUAACUUUUUAUCUUUAUUGUUGAAUCUAAUGCCUAAUGGUAUUAAUAAGAGUACUAAGUAAAUAAUUUCAGUAAAUUGAAGAUGAUAUAACCUUCUUCAUCCAAGUAUUAUAAGAAGGAAAUUGGUUAGAUGUAUGUGUGUUAUAACCAUAUUUGUUUAGAAGUCAAUUACUUUGUUUUUUUAAAAAAGUUUACUUCAUCCCAUGAUAUAACAUGAAAGAGAUCUUUGUGAAUAAAUUCAAAAAUCAAAAUAAAUCUCUGUGACUGUUAUAAAACUUUGGGUAAUAUCUUUUUGAAAUUUGUAACUAUAAAACAAAAUUAUUUUACACAUGCAGAAUAGUUUGCUCUUUCCUCUAAAAGUCCUUCUUAUCUUCUAACUCCAUUAAGCUAAUUUUACCAUGCCAAUCAAACCUAGUUGUUGUUUGUCUAGGAAUGUAAGAUACUUCUGGGAGACAAUAUAUUCACUGUUUUAAUUAGUGGCAGUAGACCUAAUCCAAUUAUUUGAAGAAAAAAAAAAUUAUUUCUUUUGGAGGGAAGUGGCUUGCCCUGACAUAAAUCACUAGUUAUUGAAGGCAAAAUUCCGUAAUGUUGAGAAUUAUUUAAAAAUAAAACUGAGACGUUAUAUUUA